GCAGAGAAGUUUCCGGGACUGGUGAGUAGUGGGCGAUUUAAAAACCCGCGAGUGUAGUUGUGACCUUCGCGGUAGGUGCCGGUUGGGGCCGGCUGUGAUUGUUAUCUUGGUGCUGCAGAGGACAGCAGAAGAGGAGAUUGGGUCAGAAAACUGCCCUGCCGCACCAGAGCACAGCGCACUAGUGGGACAGGGGUCCUGACUCAGACUUAACUGGCUGUGUCUCGUGGUUUUUCACUGUCCUGGAAAAGGCCUGAAGUGGCACUGAAAUGAGGCAUAGAUGAGGUAACGUCGAGGGAGCGGUUUGCAGGUUGCAAAGGGGCCCUACUGAUGCUGCUUAAUAGUAAACAGUGCUUACUCUAGGACGGGAGUUGUUUCCAGCUUUACGUGUAAAUCUCGCGAUAUUGUGGCCUGGGCACUAUUUCCAUUAAGGAGGAAACUGCACAGGAUAAGUCAUUUACCUGCUGUUGCACAGCUCUGGCUCUAGGAUUCAGGCUGGCUUCAGAGUCGGUGCUCUUAACCGCCAUACUAUGUUGCCUUCUGUUGUCGUUGUUGACUGUGGCCAUGUAGCUUCGCAGUUUCCUCAUCUGUAACAGUAAAUAACUCAAAACCUGCAUGAUGGCCCACUAGGGUUUCACUUUCGAGCUUGCCAGAUGUAGAAAAUGCUGGAGAAUGGAGUACUAUGAGGACCAUUAGAAGAUCUUUCAAGGCCGGACGCAGUGGCUCACCCCUGUAAUCCCGGUACUCUUGGAGGCCGAGGCAGGUGGAUCACUUGAGCGCAGGAGUUUGAGACCAGCCUGGGCAACAUGGCGAAUCCCCAUCUCUACUAAAAAUACAAAAAUUAGCCAGGUGUGGUGUUUAGCGCCUGUAGUCCCAGCUGCUCAGGAGGCUGAGGUGGGAGGAUCUGCUUGAGCUCAGGAAGUCGAGGCUGCAGUGAGCUGAGAUCACGCCACUGCACUCCAGCCUAGGCGCCUAGUGAAACCCUGUGUCAAAAAGAAAAAAACAAAAACAAACUUCCAAGACCUCGAGUGGUUUUUGGAGACCCUGUAUCACUUCAAAUAAUGUGUUAAACAAGCAUCUUCAUCUCAUUAAAUAGAAAUGUUGAAAAAUUGCUUUUGGAAUAAUUGACUUAUGGAUAUUUCAUCAAAUUUACAGUUGGCUAUGCUUUCUUAUUGUGCAUACUAUGAAAUGUUUUUCUUCAAAAAGUGUUUAUAAGUGGUAAGUUUAAGAAUGGGGUUGACAGCAUUAUCUUUUGUGGUUAUUUGAUUAAACAUUUACUAAUUGUGCAUAUUUUGGAGCCAGCAGUUUUUUUCUACCUUUCCAUUGCCCUCCCACCUUCCCUCUGUUGCCAACCUUUUCAGUUCCUUGUUGGAUGUAGAUACUUAGAAGGCUUACAGGCUGUCUGGGAAAAGUACCCUAUACCUUAUCCCCUCCCACCUCUUGAGCCUGGCCUUUGUGUAGCAAAUGUUGCUUAAGGGGCAGUGGCUUCUCCCUUCUUCUGCCUUGACCCUGCCCAUUUAUAGAGUGACCUGCCUAUGUAUUCCUUGAUUUUUGAUUCUGAUAAAGCACUUGACAUUUUAAACAUUCUUUUUUUUUUUUUUUUUCUUUUUGAGACGGAGUGUUGCUCUCUCGCCAGGCUGGAGUGCUGUGGCAUGAUCUUGGCUCACUGCAACCUCCGCCUCCCAGGUUCAAGUGAUUCUCCUGCGUCAGCCUCCCGAGUAGCUGGGACUACAGGUGCACACCACCAUGCCCAGCUAAUUUUUGUAUUUUUAGUAGAGACGGUUUCACCACGUUGGCCAGGAUAGUCUUUAUCUCUUGACUUUGUGAUCCUCCCGCCUCGGCCUCCCAAAGUGCUGGGAUUACAGGCGCCCCGCCACAUUAUUCUGUUUUUUGGUAAAGCACAUUGUAAUGCCAGUAUAUACCACCCCAACUCCAAAUUCUGUUGCAAUCAGGGGAGGCGGGCAGUGUCAUUCUAUGCAGUAAGCAUUUAGUGCUGGCUUAUAUUAGUGAUACUGAGAUUUAUUGAAGUUAGUUCCUAUUACAUAGUAGCUUUAGCAUAAUGGGCACACACAGAAUUAUGAGAAUACUGAGGGGUGGGGAGCCUUGGGAAGGAUGCUGAAAAGGGAGGUCAAGAAAAGUUUUAUUUAAGAAGUUGGAGGGGGCUUGGGAAAAGGAAAGGUAAUAUUUAGAGAAAUGGAUUAGGGAGGAGGUUGGUUGAAGCAAGGGUAGGGAGAAUAAGAACAAGGGUGUGCAAGGCAGGAGAUGGGAUGGACGUUUGUGUAUUAUGUACCAGGCUUUGCUAGGUUACAUAAUUCAUUAGCUCCUCUGGAUGGCCUGUGAAGUGGGUUAUAGUAUCUCUGUUUCGUAGGUGAGAAAACAAGAUUGGAGAGGUUAAAUGGCUUACCUAAGUUACAGUGUGCUGGUAAGUGGCAGAGCCACUAUUUGAACCCAGAUCUCUAUGACGACAGCUCUUUUGCCCAUAUGUUUUGAUGCCUCAAAGAUCCAGGCCUAAAGUAUACCUGUGUACCAUUUUCUUUGUUUUGACAUCAGAAACUUGAACUUUACCUGAUUUCUGUAUGUUGUCAUCUUGCGUACGCCCAGUCCCCACGACAGUCCGGUUUGUAGAUUCCCUGAUCUGCAAUUCUUCCCGUUCCUUCAUGGAUUUGAAGGCUCUCCUUUCUUCCUUGAAUGACUUUGCAUCCCUCUCGUUUGCUGAGAGUUGGGACAAUGUUGGAUUACUGGUGGAACCAAGCCCACCACAUACUGUAAAUACACUCUUCCUGACCAAUGACCUGACUGAGGAAGUGAUGGAGGAGGUGCUGCAAAAGAAGGCAGACCUCAUUCUCUCCUACCAUCCGCCUAUCUUCCGACCCAUGAAGCGCAUAACCUGGAACACAUGGAAGGAGCGCCUGGUGAUCCGGGCUCUGGAGAACAGAGUCGGUAUCUACUCUCCUCAUACAGCCUAUGAUGCUGCGCCCCAGGGCGUCAACAACUGGUUGGCUAAAGGGCUUGGAGCUUGUACCUCCAGGCCCAUACAUCCUUCCAAAGCUCCCAACUACCCUACAGAGGGAAACCACCGAGUAGAAUUCAACGUUAACUACACCCAAGACCUGGACAAAGUCAUGUCUGCAGUGAAAGGAAUUGACGGUGUUUCUGUCACUUCUUUUUCUGCUAGGACUGGUAAUGAGGAACAAACACGGAUUAAUCUGAAUUGUACUCAGAAGGCUUUGAUGCAGGUGGUAGAUUUUCUUUCCCGGAACAAACAACUUUAUCAGAAGACGGAAAUUCUGUCACUGGAGAAGCCUUUGCUUCUACAUACUGGAAUGGGACGGUUAUGCACACUGGAUGAAUCUGUCUCCCUGGCAACCAUGAUUGAUCGAAUAAAAAGACACCUAAAACUAUCUCAUAUUCGCUUAGCCCUUGGGGUGGGGAGAACCUUAGAGUCUCAAGUCAAAGUCGUGGCCCUGUGUGCUGGUUCUGGGAGCAGCGUUCUGCAGGGUGUUGAGGCUGACCUUUACCUCACAGGUGAGAUGUCCCAUCAUGAUACUUUGGAUGCUGCUUCCCAAGGAAUAAAUGUCAUCCUCUGUGAACACAGCAACACUGAACGAGGCUUUCUUUCUGACCUUCGAGAUAUGCUGGAUUCUCACUUGGAGAAUAAGAUAAAUAUUAUCCUAUCAGAGACUGACAGGGACCCUCUUCAGGUGGUAUAAUUGCAGAAACAUCAGGAUAACACAUUCUACAAAUCAGCUGGAUGCCAACUUAAAUUUGUAACAUGAGUCAGUGGGACUGGUGUGCUUCCAGAGAGUGUCUUCGAGGGUAUCAUCAUUUCCGGUUUGUUAAUCUUAUUCACCAAAUGUUCUAUCGCUCGUAAGGUAAAACUGUAAUAUAACUACCAUAUUAAAUAACAAAUGUUCAUUAUAAACUCUAGGAAAGAUUGAAUAAAAUCUGUUUACUUAACAUUCUU